GAGGAGUCCGUGGCCGUUGGGGCGGGAAAAAGCUGUGGAGGGUUCGAGGCUGUGGUGGUAAUUGGGUUUUCCUCAGACUUGAGGCGACGACACACUCAUUGGAAGGGGACGAGGAAUCCAGGGUGUGGCAGAAGACUGGAGAGGAGCUAAGGGGGUCGGUAUGUGGAUCCAGUGAACCCGUCCAGGUGCCCCAAGAGGCUCGUGAAUAUGGACGGACCCAUGAGGCCACGAUCGGCCUCCCUCGUUGACUUUCAGUUUGGAGUUGUCGCCACAGAGACGAUUGAAGACGCCCUGCUUCACUUGGCCCAGCAGAAUGAGCAAGCAGUGAGGGAGGCUUCGGGGCGGCUGGGCCGCUUCAGGGAGCCCCAGAUCGUGGAGUUUGUUUUUCUCCUGUCUGAACAAUGGUGUCUGGAGAAAUCUGUGAGCUACCAGGCUGUAGAAAUCCUAGAAAGGUUUAUGGUAAAACAGGCAGAGAACAUCUGCAGGCAAGCCACAAUCCAGCCAAGAGAUAAUAAGAGAGAGUCUCAGAAUUGGAGGGCUCUGAAACAGCAGCUUGUCAACAAGUUUACUCUCCGUCUUGUGUCAUGUGUUCAGCUGGCCAGCAAACUUUCCUUCCGAAACAAAAUAAUCAGCAACAUUACAGUCUUGAAUUUCCUCCAGGCUCUAGGCUAUCUACACACUAAAGAAGAACUGCUGGAAUCAGAGCUUGAUGUUUUGAAGUCCUUGAACUUCCGAAUUAAUCUGCCCACUCCCCUGGCAUAUGUGGAGACGCUCCUAGAGGUUUUAGGAUACAAUGGCUGUUUGGUUCCAGCCAUGAGGCUGCAUGCAACCUGCCUGACACUGCUCGACCUGGUCUAUCUUCUGCAUGAACCCAUAUAUGAGAGCCUGUUGAGGGCUUCAAUUGAGAACUCCACUCCCAGUCAGCUGCAAGGGGAAAAGUUUACUUCAGUGAAGGAAGACUUCAUGCUGUUGGCAGUAGGAAUCAUUGCAGCAAGUGCUUUCAUCCAAAACCAUGAGUGUUGGAGCCAGGUUGUGGGGCAUUUGCAGAGCAUCACUGGUAUUGCCUUGGCAAGCAUUGCUGAGUUCUCUUAUGCAAUCCUGACUCACGGAGUGGGAGCCAACACUCCGGGGAGACAGCAGUCUAUUCCUCCCCACCUGGCAGCCAGAGCUCUGAAGACUGUUGCUUCCUCUAACACAUGAGGGAGGCUGAAUCCACCAAAUAUAAACAGCCAUCCGUCACUGCACUCAUGCCUCCCUCUGUUUACUUUCAUACUAAGGGUACAAAAAUUCCAAGUCUCUUUUGAACUGUAUUUUGUAUGCCAAUUUCAUGCUUAUUUUUCCUUUAUCAGAGAGAGUUAAGGUGGACGAGCAUGCCCUUUUUGUCAUAUCAGCCUGAAAAUGUUAAAAAGCUAGGUGGAGACAGAUUAGUUGUUUCAUUUUUGUUUAACAAGGUAUUUAUACUUUUAGCUUAAUUUCAUUAAGAGGAACAUCAGGCAUUGCAAUCAGUAUUAAUCAGGGGCUCAAAUACAGACUAUCUGGGUGACCUUGACUAAGCAUCAAGGAGGUAGCCUUUAUUUCCCCUUAAAAUUAGUUUAACAUCUCUGUUCCAUUAUUCAGAUCUACACAAACAAGGCUUCCUCAACAGCUAUCUAUUUUUACUAGAGUCUUUUUUUAAAACUAAAACUAACUCUAAAGAAGUUUCAACAGAAUUUCCACAUACCUGCAUUCAUUAGAACUUGAUUCUCCCAGAAUACAAAGUACUCUAUUUUAAAGAAAAACCCAACAGUGCACCCCUGGGCAGUUUUCAGACUGCAGCAAAUCUUUUAUUACAAAUAAUUAAAUCUCUCCAUAAUGUCUCAAACAGUAUCAAACACCAUUUCAUAUCUCUAACACAGAGCAGAGUCGGCAUUCAGUAUAAGAACCAAGUGAAAAGUGUUAAAUUUCAAGCAUCUGAUCACAUCACAUGGUGACCAGGUAAAGCUUAGAUGUCAUUUUCCCACAUUAUCCAACUGUGCAUCUCAAACAUAUCCUCAUCUCAGUAAAGACAAAAGUUUCUAUUUCAUAUUGUUAAGUGCAGGAAGUUGAGAGAGAUAAAAAUCCAGUGAAAACACAUCAAUCUCAAUUCAACUCAGUUAAAAAAAAGAAAAGCAAAUUUAAAUUAGUUUUUUUCAGAGAAGAAAGGGAAAGGAGUCCAUGGGGUUAAGAAUCAAAACUGACCAGGGCUGGCAACUAUAGAUGGCAUGUUGUAGCUCUGGAAAGUAUCUGUCACAUGAUAUUUUAAAAUAAAGUGGCUUUUGUGGAUUUUUUCUUUUUUGGUAUUGUAAACAUGUACUGUUUAAUAUUACCCGAAUUUAAUUUAAAACAUGUUUGCAAACAAAACAAAAUUAAAAGCCUUUAAGGCAAACCUCCCCCUAAGGAAAAAAGUCAUUUGUUAUAAAAUUGUGAGGACACCCAAGCAAGACCCCACUUAAGAUUCGUCAGCAUGAACUUGAGAGCUUUUGUCCACUGCUCCUCAGAGUUAAACUGGGUUUUGAUGGAAUAGGAGCCGCCACUGCCUCCUGUGUCUUCAAUCUUGCCUUUCUCCACAUCCAUCCUGCAGAUGGACAGAGCAAAACUCAUUAGUAACUGAGAUCUGAGUUAAGUAAGUUCGGGGCAGGGACUUGAUCAUGGGACCAUUCACGUCAUUUUAUCUAUUAAAGAACACUUGGUGAGGAAUGAUAGUGUAUUUUGGAUUUGCUUGAAAGCCAAAAAUCAAGAAGACUGUCACAAGAGCCUCAUUGUCAUUGCAGAGUACAGGGACAGGACACACACCCAAAGAGAAGAGAAGCCUGGAGUAGGGGUGAGUGAGGGUUACAGUACUUCUUGCUGUUUUCCUAGGCAUCCCUGAACUUGGCGGGGGAGAAAGGAGGCAGAAGAAAAGAAAUGCUUUGUUUUGGGGUGAUAGAAGCAGCCUUACUCUAAGUAAAAACUAGAGUUUCCAUCCAUCAAUGGGAUCCUAGAAAAAUCAAAAGAAGCAUUCCUGUGUAUUUCCAAGGGCUUCAGGGAAAAACCUUCUUGAAACUGGAGAGGAGGCUUGAGCUCUAUGCCAAGAAAACCCCCUAAACCAUCUAAGGCAACAUUCUUCUACUCCAAGGACUAGGUGGUCACAUUCUGUCCUGCUUGCAGUACUGGGUCAGUCUCUGCCCAUCAAUGUCAUGUGAUUCUGUGCCAUUUUUUUGCUUUCCCACCAUUUAUACUGUUUUGCCUCCAUUA